AUGUGGUCAUCACUUGGAAAUGCUCAAUUUAAUCAGGCAACUGCUGGGUGUGGGCAGGGAUCCCAGCAGCACCCACUGGCGUCGGCUGCCUCCCACAAUGCCAGCCCCCAGUAUCACUUGGUAGACAAACUGCUUUUUGCACUACAACCUCCAGAAGAAAGCGCGAACGCAAUUCCCCACCACCACAAAUUACAGUCCAGUUUCCCCACAUGUGGAAGUAACAGGAGUCAGUCAGCACAUACUGAGUACAAUGGAGAAAUCGCCCCCGAGAAACAUCAACUUCAUGGCCGUAUUUUCUCCUGUUACGUAAGUACGAAUGAACGCACCUCCGCCCUGCCACAGCUCCAUACGCCUCACCCCUUACACGCACGGUCACUUGCCCCGCGCAUUCCCCCACCCCGCCCCCAUGCCGCCUCAAGUCCUCCUAGCCCUGACACACAGCUGGGACUAUCACGUCCAACCGGAGGUCCUGGACUAGCUCCCACAGCACGAGAAAUCUUUCGUGGCGAAGCAGCAGCCCCUGAGCUGCCUCCUCUGCAUAGGAAUCGCCCUAUCUGUGAUGUCACCGACAGCGCCUUUCCCGUCCCCGUCUGCUCUUCCGCCCCACCCUCUGCCACUCGGCCGACCAACCAGCUGCGGGAGCGGGCGGAGGAAGUGACACCUGACUCUACCUCCUUUCCCUCCCAUCCCCGUCCCUGGUCUCUCCCAAAGAAACUACAACACCAAACUCUGAGAAUACUCCACAGACUUAUUAAUGGUUUCCACCCCCGUCUCUGCAAAUCUAUCAGGCAAGUUUUUCCUGCCCUUUACUUUCAUAUAAGCUGAGUCACAGUCUGUAGUGGGUUUUGGGGGGAGUGUUACUGCCCAACAGGUACACCCUGCCUGCUGCCUAGACAGAGCCAAUUUUUCGACACAGGGGAAUUGCAAUAAAGAGCUGCACUCUUUAUUUGGUGAUUGGGGGCCGGUGAAUUGAGAGUUCUGCUUGGCCAGGUCGGAGAUGAAAUCACA